AUGCACUCAAGCAGAGAAGAAAUCCACAAAGACUCACAGUCUGCUGGUGGGCAGAGAAGACAGAAACGACAUGAGCACAGCAGGAAAAGAAAGUUGUCUGACAGAAGUUUGAUGAGAGGAAUUUGACUCAGAAGACUGAAAUAUCCUUUAACCUUACUAUAAAAUAUCUUACAAAAUACUCAUUGAUUUCACAGCAUUAGAAUCAUCAAGGUAAUCAAAUGCAAAGCAGCUGUGCUAUGGGAGGUAAAGAAACCCUUUUCCAUUGAGGAUGUGGAGGUUGCACCUCCUAAGGCUUAUGAAGUUCGCAUUAAGAUGGUGGCUGUAGGAAUCUGUCACACAGAUGACCACGUGGUUAGUGGCAACCUGGUGACCCCCCUUCCUGUGAUUUUAGGCCAUGAGGCAGCCGGCAUCGUGGAGAGUGUUGGAGAAGGGGUGACUACAGUCAAACCAGGUGAUAAAGUCAUCCCGCUCUUUACUCCUCAGUGUGGAAAAUGCAGAGUUUGUAAAAACCCGGAGAGCAACUACUGCUUGAAAAAUGAUCUAGGCAAUCCUCGGGGGACCCUGCAGGAUGGCACCAGGAGGUUCACCUGCAGGGGGAAGCCCAUUCACCACUUCCUUGGCACCAGCACCUUCUCCCAGUACACGGUGGUGGAUGAGAAUGCAGUGGCCAAAAUUGAUGCAGCCUCGCCCCUGGAGAAAGUCUGCCUCAUUGGCUGUGGAUUCUCGACUGGUUAUGGGUCUGCAGUUAACGUUGCCAAGGUCACCCCAGGCUCUACCUGUGCUGUGUUUGGCCUGGGAGGGGUCGGCCUAUCUGCUGUUAUGGGCUGUAAAGCAGCUGGAGCAGCCAGAAUCAUUGCGGUGGACAUCAACAAGGACAAAUUUGCAAAGGCCAAAGAGUUGGGUGCCACUGAAUGCAUCAACCCUCAAGACUACAAGAAACCCAUUCAGGAAGUGCUAAAGGAAAUGACUGAUGGAGGUGUGGAUUUUUCGUUUGAAGUCAUCGGUCGGCUUGACACCAUGAUGGCUUCCCUGUUAUGUUGUCAUGAGGCAUGUGGCACAAGCGUCAUCGUAGGGGUACCUCCUGCUUCCCAGAACCUCUCAAUAAACCCUAUGCUGCUACUGACUGGACGCACCUGGAAGGGGGCUGUUUAUGGUGGCUUUAAGAGUAAAGAAGGUAUCCCAAAACUUGUGGCUGAUUUUAUGGCUAAGAAGUUUUCACUGGAUGCGUUAAUAACCCAUGUUUUACCUUUUGAAAAAAUAAAUGAAGGAUUUGACCUGCUUCACUCUGGGAAAAGUAUCCGUACCGUCCUGACGUUUUGAGGCAAUAGAGAUGCCUUCCCCUGUAGCAGUCUUCAGCCUCCUCUACCCUACAAGAUCUGGAGCAACAGCUAGGAAAUAUCAUUAAUUCAGCUCUUCAGAGAUGUUAUCAAUAAAUUACACAUGGGGGCUUUCCAAAGAAAUGGAAAUUGAUGGGAAAUUAUUUUUCAGGAAAAUUUAAAAUUCAAGUGAGAAGUAAAUAAAGUGUUGAACAUCAGCUGGGGAAUUGAAGCCAACAAACCUUCCUUCUUAACCAUUCUACUGUGUCACCUUUGCCAUUGAGGAAAAAUAUUCCUGUGACUUCUUGCAUUUUUGGUAUCUUCAUAAUCUUUAGUCAUCGAAUCCCAGUGGAGGGGACCCUUUUACUUGCCCUGAACAUACACAUGCUGGGCCAUUGUGAUUGAAGUCUUCUAACUCUGUCUCAGUUUUCACUGUCGACAUUUUCCUUUUUCUAAUAAAAAUGUACCAAAUCCCUGGGGUAAAAGCUAGGGUAAGGUAAAGGAUAGACUCACAUUUACAAGUAGUGAAGGUCCAAGAGUUCUAAAUACAGGAAAUUUCUUAGGAACUCAAAUAAAAUGCCCCACAUUUUACUACAGUAAAUGGCAGUGUUUUUAUGACUUUUAUACUAUUUCUUUAUGGUCGAUAUACAAUUGAUUUUUUAAAAUAAUAGCAGAUUUCUUGCUUCAUAUGACAAAGCCUCAAUUACUAAUUGUAAAAACUGAACUAUUCCCAGAAUCAUGUUCAAAAAAUCUGUAAUUUUUGCUGAUGAAAGUGCUUCAUUGACUAAACAGUAUUAGUUUGUGGCUAUAAAUGAUUAUUUAGAUGAUGACUGAAAAUGUGUAUAAAGUAAUUAAAAGUAAUAUGGUGGCUUUAAGUGUAGAGAUGGGAUGGCAAAUGCUGUGAAUGCAGAAUGUAAAAUUGGUAACUAAGAAAUGGCACAAACACCUUAAGCAAUAUAUUUUCCUAGUAGAUAUAUAUAUACACAUACAUAUAUACACAUAUACAAAUGUAUAUUUUUGCAAAAUUGUUUUCAAUCUAGAACUUUUCUAUUAACUACCAUGUCUUAAAAUCAAGUCUAUAAUCCUAGCAUUAGUUUAAUAUUUUGAAUAUGUAAAGACCUGUGUUAAUGCUUUGUUAAUGCUUUUCCCACUCUCAUUUGUUAAUGCUUUCCCACUCUCAGGGGAAGGAUUUGCAUUUUGAGCUUUAUCUCUAAAUGUGACAUGCAAAGAUUAUUCCUGGUAAAGGAGGUAGCUGUCUCCAAAAAUGCUAUUGUUGCAAUAUCUACAUUCUAUUUCAUAUUAUGAAAGACCUUAGACAUAAAGUAAAAUAGUUUAUCAUUUACUGUGUGAUCUUCAGUAAGUCUCUCAGGCUCUCUGAGCUUGUUCAUCCUUUGUUUUGAAAAAAUUACUCAACCAAUCCAUUACAGCUUAACCAAGAUUAAAUGGGAUGAUGUUAAUGAAAGAGCUUCGCCAAUUAAGAAGGGCCAUGUAAAUGUGGGUAACCUGAUUGUUUUGUCAAAAAUGCUAAAGCGGGGUGGGGGGUGGCGCAGUGGCUUAUCCCUGUAAUCCCAGCACUUUGGGAGGUCAAGACGGGUGGAUGACCUGAGGUCAGGAGUUUGAGACCAGCCUGGUCAACAUGGUGAAACCCCAUCUCUACUAAAAAUACAAAAAUUUGCCAGGCAUGGUGGCAGGUGGCUGUAAUCCCAGCUACUCAGGAGGCUGAGGCAAGAGAAUCGCUGGAGCCUGGGAGGCGGAGGUUGCAGUGAGCAGAAAUCUUGCCACUGCACAGCAGCCUAGGCGACAAGAGCAAAACUCUGUCAAAAGAAAAGAAAAGAAAAUGCUGAAGGAGUUACUCAGGGUCAAGAAAGUUUUCAGAAUGUCCGUAAGAUAACAUCAUCAUGGGACACUACCUGUUGCUGGGUGCUCUGCGGCUUUUACACUGAUGCUGAUUGUGUGAGAUCCAGAAAAAGAAAAUGGAGUUCUACAUGCCCAUCUCACAGCAGGGUCAUCAAAUCCUGCUAGUGACACAGAAGCUGACAUCCAGCUCCCACCCGCCUUCCUCCCAGGUUCGGGGAGCAGGUAGAGUGGGAGCCAUUAGGUGGGCUCUGCCAGUGUUGUCAUAGAGUGGCAAGUCCUCCAUGGGAUGGGAGUGGCAUGUGGGAGCCUUCUGCAUCAUGCACUAUGAAAAAAGAAAAUUUACUAUGGGGCAAGUGGUUCAUAUAGUUAAGUGAUUGUAUAUAUAUAUAUAUAUAUAUAUAUAUAUAUAUAUAUAUAUAUAUAUACACUAUGGGGCAAGUGGUUCAUAUAGUUAAGUGAUUGUAUAUAUAUAUAUAUAUAUAUAUGUAUUCCAGUGUAGAAAGUAUUGGCUGGGUCUGUAAUCAAGUAUUCCACAGAAGUGCCUUCAUAGGUGCUGAAACAGGAUUAUGAGAGUGACAGACACAGGACUGAAGACAGGGAGAAAAUGUGCAUGGCUGUGAGAAUAUAUUGCUUUGAUUCUUUGACUUCUCAUGAUAUAUGAAAACAAAUAAAGUGGGGGGGGGUGACUUCAAUAAUAUCACGAACAUAUUUAAAAUGAAAUUCUGAGCAUGGAGAAAAAUUUCAAAUUCUGGUAUAAACAAAUAAUCUAAAAAUAUAGAUAAGGAAAAAAUGUUUUCAUUUUUUUGGUCAUAUUGAUUUGGGUCAUAUAUGAUUGACCAAAAAAAAAGAUAUUUCUAAAAUCCUGGUGCUUUUUCAUUUAAAAAUAGACAACCAAAGAGGAAAAUGAACAAUGAUGGAAAUUCGUGGAAGAGGAAACUAAAAUGGCAAAAUAGCAUAUUAAAUGGCACUGAGCCUUGGUGUGAUCAAAAAAAAAAAUAAAGCAAAAUGAGAUAUUA